GCUCCCGGCGCGGCGCUGCCCAGGGCACACUUGACCGAGGUCGGGCUGCGGGGAAAGGCGGGUCUGGGGAGAACCCCGAGAGACGCGGCGUCCUCCAACUCCUCCUCCUUCUCCUCGCGGCCGCCGAAGCCACAGCCCGAGCCCGAGCCCGAGCCCGAGCCGGCGCCACCGCGCCCCCGGCCAUGGCUUUUGCCAAUUUCCGCCGCAUCCUGCGCCUGUCUACCUUCGAGAAGAGAAAGUCCCGCGAAUAUGAGCACGUCCGCCGCGACCUGGACCCCAACGAGGUGUGGGAGAUCGUGGGCGAGCUGGGCGACGGCGCCUUCGGCAAGGUUUACAAGGCCAAGAAUAAGGAGACGGGUGCUUUGGCUGCGGCCAAAGUCAUUGAAACCAAGAGUGAGGAGGAGCUGGAGGACUACAUCGUGGAGAUUGAGAUCCUGGCCACCUGCGACCACCCCUACAUUGUGAAGCUCCUGGGAGCCUACUAUCACGACGGGAAGCUGUGGAUCAUGAUUGAGUUCUGUCCAGGGGGAGCCGUGGACGCCAUCAUGCUGGAGCUGGACAGAGGCCUCACGGAGCCCCAGAUACAGGUGGUUUGCCGCCAGAUGCUAGAAGCCCUCAACUUCCUGCACAGCAAGAGGAUCAUCCACCGAGAUCUGAAAGCUGGCAACGUGCUGAUGACCCUCGAGGGAGACAUCAGGCUGGCUGACUUUGGUGUGUCUGCCAAGAAUCUGAAGACUCUACAGAAACGAGAUUCCUUCAUCGGCACGCCUUACUGGAUGGCCCCCGAGGUGGUCAUGUGUGAGACCAUGAAAGACACGCCCUACGACUACAAAGCCGACAUCUGGUCCCUGGGCAUCACGCUGAUUGAGAUGGCCCAGAUCGAGCCGCCACACCACGAGCUCAACCCCAUGCGGGUCCUGCUAAAGAUCGCCAAGUCGGACCCUCCCACGCUGCUCACGCCCUCUAAGUGGUCUGUAGAGUUCCGUGACUUCCUGAAGAUAGCCCUGGAUAAGAACCCAGAAACCCGACCCAGUGCCGCGCAGCUGCUGGAGCAUCCCUUCGUCAGCAGCAUCACCAGUAACAAGGCUCUGCGGGAGCUGGUGGCUGAGGCCAAGGCCGAGGUGAUGGAAGAGAUCGAAGACGGCCGGGAUGAGGGGGAAGAGGAGGACGCCGUGGAUGCCGCCUCCACCCUGGAGAACCAUACUCAGAACUCCUCUGAGGUGAGUCCGCCAAGCCUCAAUGCUGACAAGCCUCUCGAGGAGUCACCUUCCACCCCGCUGGCACCCAGCCAGUCUCAGGACAGUGUGAAUGAGCCCUGCAGCCAGCCCUCUGGGGACAGAUCCCUCCAAACCACCAGUCCCCCAGUCGUGGCCCCUGGAAAUGAGAACGGCCUGGCAGUGCCUGUGCCCCUGCGGAAGUCCCGACCCGUGUCAAUGGAUGCCAGAAUUCAGGUAGCCCAGGAGAAGCAAGUUGCUGAGCAGGGUGGGGACCUCAGCCCAGCAGCCAACAGAUCUCAAAAGGCCAGCCAGAGCCGGCCCAACAGCAGCGCCCUGGAGACCUUGGGUGGGGAGAAGCUGGCCAAUGGCAGCCUGGAGCCACCUGCCCAGGCAGCUCCAGGGCCUUCCAAGAGGGACUCGGACUGCAGCAGCCUCUGCACCUCUGAGAGCAUGGACUAUGGUACCAAUCUCUCCACUGACCUGUCGCUGAACAAAGAGAUGGGCUCUCUGUCCAUCAAGGACCCGAAACUGUACAAAAAAACCCUCAAGCGGACACGCAAAUUUGUGGUGGAUGGUGUGGAGGUGAGCAUCACCACCUCCAAGAUCAUCAGCGAAGAUGAGAAGAAGGAUGAGGAGAUGAGAUUUCUCAGGCGCCAGGAACUCCGAGAGCUUCGGCUGCUCCAGAAAGAAGAGCAUCGGAACCAGACCCAGCUGAGUAACAAGCAUGAGCUGCAGCUGGAGCAAAUGCAUAAACGUUUUGAACAGGAAAUCAACGCCAAGAAGAAGUUCUUUGACACGGAAUUAGAGAACCUGGAGCGUCAGCAAAAGCAGCAAGUGGAGAAGAUGGAGCAAGACCAUGCCGUGCGCCGCCGGGAGGAGGCCAGGCGGAUCCGCCUGGAGCAGGAUCGGGACUACACCAGGUUCCAAGAGCAGCUCAAACUGAUGAAGAAAGAGGUGAAGAACGAGGUGGAGAAGCUCCCCCGACAGCAGCGGAAGGAAAGCAUGAAGCAGAAGAUGGAGGAGCACACGCAGAAAAAGCAGCUUCUUGACCGGGACUUUGUAGCCAAGCAGAAGGAGGACCUGGAGCUGGCCAUGAAGAGGCUCACCACCGACAACAGGCGGGAGAUCUGUGACAAGGAGCGCGAGUGCCUCAUGAAGAAGCAGGAGCUCCUUCGAGACCGGGAAGCAGCCCUGUGGGAGAUGGAAGAGCACCAGCUGCAGGAGAGGCACCAGCUGGUGAAGCAGCAGCUCAAAGACCAGUACUUCCUCCAGCGGCACGAGCUGCUGCGCAAGCAUGAGAAGGAGCGGGAGCAGAUGCAGCGCUACAACCAGCGCAUGAUAGAGCAGCUGAAGGUGCGGCAGCAACAGGAAAAGGCGCGGCUGCCCAAGAUCCAGAGGAGUGAGGGCAAGACGCGCAUGGCCAUGUACAAGAAGAGCCUCCACAUCAACGGCGGGGGCAGCGCAGCUGAGCAGCGUGAGAAGAUCAAGCAGUUCUCCCAGCAGGAGGAGAAGAGGCAGAAGUCGGAGCGGCUGCAGCAACAGCAGAAACACGAGAACCAGAUGCGGGACAUGCUGGCGCAGUGUGAGAGCAACAUGAGCGAGCUGCAGCAGCUGCAGAAUGAAAAGUGCCACCUCCUGGUAGAGCACGAAACCCAGAAACUGAAGGCCCUGGAUGAGAGCCAUAACCAGAACCUGAAGGAAUGGCGGGACAAGCUUCGGCCGCGCAAGAAGGCUCUGGAAGAGGAUCUGAACCAGAAGAAGCGGGAGCAGGAGAUGUUCUUCAAGCUGAGCGAGGAGGCGGAGUGCCCAAACCCCUCCACCCCAAGCAAGGCCGCCAAGUUCUUCCCCUACAGUUCUGCGGAUGCUUCUUAACAACCGCCCGGGGCUGUGGCUGGCAGCUUGGUGGGCCCCAGGGCCUUCUCCUUCAUUCUCUGUGAACAUGUAACUCAGGACCCCUUUUCCCUCUUGCGUCUGUGCCAGCUCAAAUCCAGCCCCUCGCCCUGUGCCACCCCAACUGUGCCUGAUAGACCUGCCCCAGCGUUCCUGACUUCUUGCUGGCCUGUGGAGGGUGAGGUGUAAUUAUUUGUCACCUGAACCUAAUGUAUAUUCUCCUUGAGCCCCAGAUCCCUUCAAGCUGGAAGGGAUGGGGCUGUUGGUGGGGUCAGGGUCCAAGAGGAAUGGGUGUUCUGUGGCCUCGAGUCCUCUCCUGUUUGCGAAAAUACCAGUUUUGCUCUCUGUGGGACAAAGCACUGCUGAUGAAGUCCCCGUGGGCUCAUCCGGGCUGGAAUUCUUGGUUUUUCAGCCAUUCCCUGCAGAGUCACUCAAUCAUCAAGUCCCUCACAGCCAUUUCUGUUCCCAGAGGAGCCAGGCCUGCAGCUGGCUGCUCAGGAGAUGGCCUCAUUCCUCCUGUUCUCCCAGUUUGCUUUCCACUUAAGACAAAGCCUUGUCUAUGUGGGGGGCGGGGACCGGGGAAAGAGGGAGGCUGAAAUGUUUAUUCUGCUUCUCCCGUGUUUCAUGCCAUCUCGCGUCCCCCUUCCUGCACAUGGGUGUGAAUGCACACACAUACGCGUACACACAGGACUUGGUCUGCUGGCCUGGCCUCUUCUGCCCAGGUGGGUUGGAACACGUUUGCUGCCUGAGCCUGUGCCACUGAGCAUGUUAGGUGGAGCAGUUGGUGUGGCACGUGCGGGGUGUUGGCACCGGAGGCAUGGAAAAGCACAGGCUGUACUGCCAGGCUGCGAUGCGUGCUGGCCCCCGCACAGGCUCCUGUGUGCAGGGACUGAUUCCUCAGCACACGAGGCUUCCACAACCCAGUCUGCUCCAUAGCACUCUGGCCCACCCUGUCUGCAGGUGAAACAGGAGGGCUGUUUGCCUCUGCCCCAUCCCCCCGACUGUGUUCAGGAGUCCCACCUUGCAUUUCAGACCUGGGCUGGCAGUCUGUUGGACUUCUCUUCAGGAAGAAAAAGCAUCAGGGGGAAAUGGAAUGCCCCUGCCCCAGGAACAUGGCAGAAGCACAGGUUCUGUACCUCAGAUGGACUCCUGCUGGGCCUUCGGGGUCUCAGUUGGCUUCCCCCAGAUUCUGAUUCUACAGCUGCAGAAUGUAUAUAACGCAAUAAAAGCAAAUGUUUGAACCAGUAUGCGGGUUUACUUACAAGGAAACCUUUUUUCACCCUGAUUUCUAAUUAUUUUAUUGAAACAACUAUAAAAUGUAUGGUUUCUCCAGGAAGAUAUCUGCUUUUUAAAACAACAAACAAGAACAACAACACAAAACUGGUAAUGAUUUGGAGUAAUCAUGCGGGCAUAUUGAGUCUGGGUAGUGUUUCGCUGGUGGUAGAGUGGUUGAGACUUCCUGGGAGGACUUUUUCCGCCUUCACUCCUACAGAUUUAAGAUUCUUUAUUUUUAGGCCGGGCAUGGUGACUCACCUGAGGUGAGGAGUUCGAGACUAGCCUGGCCAACAUGGCAAAACCCUGUCUCUACUAAAAGUACAAAAAUUAGCCAGGCGUGGUGGUGCAUGCCUAUAAUCCCAGCUACUCGGGAGGCUGAGGCAGGAGAAUCGCUUGAACCCAGGAGGCAGAGGUUGCAGUAAGCCAAGGUCACACCACUGCACUCCAGCCUAGGUGACAGGGCGAGACUCUGUCUCUCAAAAAAAAAAAAAAAAAAAAUUCUUUGAGACAGGGUCUCUAAUAUGUUGCCCAAGCUGAUCUCAAACUCGUGGCUCAACUGAUUCUCCCGCUUCAACCUUGAGUAGCUGGGACGACAGAUACAUGCUACUGCACCCAGCUAGGUUAAGGUUCUGUAUACUCUGUCUUUCUAAAGCAAUUCCCUGGAAAUUUUCUCAACAUUGGUUAUAACUGAAUGCUUGGGAAGGGAGGGGCAGCCCUUCAACAGGAAAAGGGGACUGCCCAAAUCUUAAAUGCACAGUCAAGAUUCUCUUGGAGCUAGCAAUGGUUCUCAGGUUAGUGAGCAUUUAGCUUGCCUGCUGCAGAAUUUGACCCAGAUGGGGGUGUUUUUUAGGUCUCUCACAAAUGAGACAAGCGAAACAAUUGUCUCCUUUUAUUCUCUUUGGUGCAUUGGUGCUGGGGAAACAUGAACUAGCGGCAGUGUAACUGCAGAACAUAGACCCAGUUCUACCAGGCCAGGCCAGCGUUGGGAACCACCAGACAGGGCUGCUUUGGGCUUUGCUUACAGUAUUUCCAUGUGUAGCCUGGCGUGUGAGAAAGUAUUAGGUGAAAUGCCAGUUUCAUGGUUCAGGUGAAAGUCUGUGAUCAUUCCCCUCGUGGCUCGUCCUUCACAUCACUUUUGCCCUUCAAGGAGUUGCCGCGUCCCCGCUCAGUGCCGCCUGAGCCCUCAGAGCUCCCCUGUGCUUUUCUGGAUGGGGACUGGCGGGGUCACCUAGCCUCACCGUGGAGCCACCGUGCAAUGCCCAUCUCUGAGAGGCCCACGCGGUAUUCCUCGUGCCCUGUGUUAGUGCUUUCUGUAUAAGGGACAGACAGAACUGGGUUUUUUUCCUCUGUCUGGUUUUAGAGUAAAUGUAACUAACUUUUAUUUUCCCUUUAUGAAAGAUAGAAAUUAUUUUUAUGUAGUUUCCAGACUUUAUACAAAAUUUUUGUAAAAUGUUCUCUGGAAAGUUAACUACAAGAAUGUAAAUAUGCUUCUAAUAAAAUAACAAGGUUA